GCAGACUUAGCCGUGCAUUGCAGGCAUGGAGGAUUAAUCAGUGACAGGAAGCUGCGUCUCUCGGAGCGGUGACCAGCUGUGGUCAGGAGAGCCUCAGCAGGGCCAGCCCCAGGAGUCUUUCCCGAUUCUUGCUCACUGCUCACCCACCUGCUGCUGCCAUGAGGCACCUUGGGGCCUUCCUCUUCCUUCUGGGGGUCCUGGGGGCCCUCACUGAGAUGUGUGAAAUACCAGAGAUGGACAGCCAUCUGGUAGAGAAGUUGGGCCAGCACCUCUUACCUUGGAUGGACCGGCUUUCCCUGGAGCACUUGAACCCCAGCAUCUAUGUGGGCCUACGCCUCUCCAGUCUGCAGGCUGGGACCAAGGAAGACCUCUACCUGCACAGCCUCAAGCUUGGUUACCAGCAGUGCCUCCUAGGGUCUGCCUUCAGCGAGGAUGACGGUGACUGCCAGGGCAAGCCUUCCAUGGGCCAGCUGGCCCUCUACCUGCUCGCUCUCAGAGCCAACUGUGAGUUUGUCAGGGGCCACAAGGGGGACAGGCUGGUCUCACAGCUCAAAUGGUUCCUGGAGGAUGAGAAGAGAGCCAUUGGGCAUGAUCACAAGGGCCACCCCCACACUAGCUACUACCAGUAUGGCCUGGGCAUUCUGGCCCUGUGUCUCCACCAGAAGCGGGUCCAUGACAGCGUGGUGGACAAACUUCUGUAUGCUGUGGAACCUUUCCACCAGGGCCACCAUUCUGUGGACACAGCAGCCAUGGCAGGCUUGGCAUUCACCUGUCUGAAGCGCUCAAACUUCAACCCUGGUCGGAGACAACGGAUCACCAUGGCCAUCAGAACAGUGCGAGAGGAGAUCUUGAAGGCCCAGACCCCCGAGGGCCACUUUGGGAAUGUCUACAGCACCCCAUUGGCAUUACAGUUCCUCAUGACUUCCCCCAUGCGUGGGGCAGAACUGGGAACAGCAUGUCUCAAGGCGAGGGUUGCUUUGCUGGCCAGUCUGCAGGAUGGAGCCUUCCAGAAUGCUCUCAUGAUUUCCCAGCUGCUGCCCGUUCUGAACCACAAGACCUACAUUGAUCUGAUCUUCCCAGACUGUCUGGCACCACGAGUCAUGUUGGAACCAGCUGCUGAGACCAUUCCUCAGACCCAAGAGAUCAUCAGUGUCACGCUGCAGGUGCUUAGUCUCUUGCCGCCGUACAGACAGUCCAUCUCUGUUCUGGCCGGGUCCACCGUGGAAGAUGUCCUGAAGAAGGCCCAUGAGUUAGGAGGAUUCACAUAUGAAACACAGGCCUCCUUGUCAGGCCCCUACUUAACCUCCGUGAUGGGGAAAGCGGCCGGAGAAAGGGAGUUCUGGCAGCUUCUCCGAGACCCCAACACCCCACUGUUGCAAGGUAUUGCUGACUACAGACCCAAGGAUGGAGAAACCAUUGAGCUGAGGCUGGUUAGCUGGUAGCCCCUGAGCUCCCUCAUCCCAGCAGCCUCGCACACUCCCUAGGCUUCUACCCUCCCUCCUGAUGUCCCUGGAACAGGAACUCGCCUGACCCUGCUGCCACCUCCUGUGCACUUUGAGCAAUGCCCCCUGGGAUCACCCCAGCCACAAGCCCUUCGAGGGCCCUAUACCAUGGCCCACCUUGGAGCAGAGAGCCAAGCAUCUUCCCUGGGAAGUCUUUCUGGCCAAGUCUGGCCAGCCUGGCCCUGCAGGUCUCCCAUGAAGGCCACCCCAUGGUCUGAUGGGCAUGAAGCAUCUCAGACUCCUUGGCAAAAAACGGAGUCCGCAGGCCGCAGGUGUUGUGAAGACCACUCGUUCUGUGGUUGGGGUCCUGCAAGAAGGCCUCCUCAGCCCGGGGGCUAUGGCCCUGACCCCAGCUCUCCACUCUGCUGUUAGAGUGGCAGCUCCGAGCUGGUUGUGGCACAGUAGCUGGGGAGACCUCAGCAGGGCUGCUCAGUGCCUGCCUCUGACAAAAUUAAAGCAUUGAUGGCCUGUGGACCUGCUACAGUGGCCUGGUGCCUCAUACUCCUCAGGUGCAGGGGCAGGGACAAGAGAAGGGGGAAGUAACCCCAUCAGGGAGGAGUGGAGGGUGCCUGAGCCGCCAUGUGGGCAUUGGGGGAGUGAUGGGAAUGCCAGCAGUGAUGACAUUGACUACUGACUGAGCACCCACUACUAUGACUGAGCACUCACUCGCUAGAUACUAUCUUGAACUGC